CUCUUGUUUUUAGUCUCGCUUUUCGGUUGCCGUUGUCUUUUUUCCUUGACUCGGAAAUGUCCGGUCGUGGUAAGCAGGGUGGCAAGGCGCGCGCCAAGGCUAAGUCGCGCUCGUCGCGCGCGGGGCUGCAGUUCCCCGUGGGCCGCGUGCACCGGUUGCUCCGCAAGGGCAACUAUUCGGAGCGCGUGGGCGCCGGCGCCCCGGUCUAUCUGGCCGCGGUGCUCGAGUACUUGACUGCCGAGAUCCUGGAGCUUGCCGGCAACGCGGCGCGCGACAACAAGAAGACGCGCAUCAUCCCGCGCCACCUGCAGCUGGCCAUCCGCAACGACGAGGAGCUCAACAAGCUGCUGGGCCGCGUGACCAUCGCGCAGGGUGGCGUCCUGCCCAACAUCCAGGCCGUACUGCUGCCCAAGAAGACGGAGAGCCACCACAAGGCCAAGGGCAAGUGAGGCCGCCCGCCGCCCCCGGGGCCCCUUUGAUGGACAUAAAGGCUCUUUUCAGAGCCACCUA